GCUCUGUGUGGCCGCUGCCGCCAUGUUGUUGUGGUUGUGAGAAGGCGGCGGCGGCGGCGGAGUAGCAGCCGGACGAGACGUCCCAGCGGCUCAGGCGCUGCCCAGCGCCGGCCCUGGCAGGGAGCCUGGUGGGGUGGCGGAGGGGGAGACUGUGCCGUGGAGGGCCUCGCCAUGUCCUGCUGCCCGACUUCCUUGUGAAACCUCCUAGUAGAAAAAGUUCUUGGGACAAACUUCAUUUGACUUCACCAUAAGGGAAAGAAGAGAGCCUUGUUGGACACUGAAGAAGGGACGGGGAUUUCUCCUCCUAAUCUGGGCCUCUUGUCAUGGAUGAAGAGACUCGGCACAGCCUUGAGUGCAUCCAGGCCAAUCAGAUCUUUCCCAGGAAGCAGCUGAUCCGGGAGGAUGAGAAUCUUCAGGUUCCUUUCCUUGAACUUCAUGGAGAGAGCACAGAGUUUGUGGGCCGUGCCGAGGAUGCCAUCAUUGCCCUUUCCAAUUACAGACUUCACAUCAAGUUCAAGGAGUCUCUUGUUAAUGUUCCAUUACAGCUUAUAGAAAGUGUUGAAUGCCGAGAUAUAUUUCAGCUUCAUUUGACUUGCAAAGACUGCAAAGUUAUCAGGUGUCAGUUUUCAACCUUUGAGCAGUGUCAAGAGUGGCUGAAGAGACUGAACAACGCAAUCCGACCACCUGCUAAAAUAGAAGAUCUCUUCUCAUUUGCAUACCAUGCUUGGUGCAUGGAGGUCUAUGCCAGUGAAAAAGAGCAACAUGGAGACCUGUGCAGACCAGGGGAGCAUGUAACUUCAAGGUUUAAAAACGAGGUGGAGAGGAUGGGUUUUGAUAUGAACAACGCCUGGAGGAUUUCCAACAUCAAUGAGAAGUACAAAUUAUGUGGUAGCUAUCCUCAAGAGCUCAUAGUGCCUGCCUGGAUCACUGACAAAGAACUGGAAAGUGUAUCAAGUUUCAGGUCCUGGAAGCGCAUCCCUGCCGUCAUCUACAGGCACCAGAGCAAUGGAGCUGUCAUUGCCCGCUGUGGACAGCCAGAGGUUAGCUGGUGGGGCUGGCGAAAUGCAGAUGAUGAGCAUCUGGUACAGUCAGUAGCCAAAGCUUGUGCCUCUGACUCCCGAUCGAGUGGCAGCAAGCUGUCAACUAGGAACACUUCUCGAGACUUUCCCAAUGGGGGAGACCUUUCUGACGUGGAGUUCGAUUCUUCUCUGUCAAAUGCUUCAGGAGCAGAGAGUUUAGCCAUCCAACCGCAGAAGCUUUUGAUCUUGGAUGCACGCUCCUAUGCAGCUGCUGUGGCAAACCGAGCCAAAGGAGGAGGCUGCGAAUGCCCAGAGUAUUACCCAAACUGUGAAGUUGUGUUUAUGGGGAUGGCAAACAUUCAUUCUAUUCGGAGGAGUUUUCAGUCUCUGCGGUUGCUGUGCACUCAGAUGCCAGAUCCGGGAAAUUGGCUAUCAGCUCUUGAAAGCACAAAAUGGCUCCAUCACUUGUCUGUGCUUCUGAAAUCAGCGCUUCUGGUAGUGCAUGCUGUGGAUCAGGAUCAGCGGCCGGUGCUAGUACACUGCUCAGAUGGCUGGGACCGCACCCCCCAGAUUGUGGCAUUGGCUAAGCUCUUGCUGGACCCUUAUUACCGAACCAUAGAGGGUUUCCAGGUCCUCGUGGAAAUGGAGUGGCUGGAUUUUGGCCAUAAAUUUGCUGACCGGUGUGGUCAUGGGGAGAACUCGGAUGAUCUGAAUGAACGUUGCCCAGUGUUUCUGCAGUGGCUUGACUGUGUUCAUCAGCUUCAGAGGCAAUUUCCUUGCUCUUUUGAGUUCAAUGAAGCAUUCCUUGUGAAACUGGUGCAGCAUACCUAUUCCUGCCUGUUUGGAACAUUCCUGUGCAACAACGCCAAGGAGAGAGGGGAAAAGCAUACUCAGGAACGGACAUGUUCCGUGUGGUCACUUCUUCGGGCAGGCAACAAGGCUUUCAAAAACCUACUGUAUUCCUCUCAGUCAGAAGCCGUGCUGUACCCUGUGUGCCAUGUGCGUAACCUGAUGCUGUGGAGUGCAGUGUACCUGCCCUGCCCAUCCCCAACCACCCCUGUGGACGACAGCUGUGCACCAUACCCAGCCCCAGGCACCAGCCCUGAUGAUCCCCCCCUGAGCCGGCUACCAAAGACUAGAUCAUACGACAAUCUGACCACAGCCUGUGACAACACAGUGCCUCUGGCCAGCCGGCGCUGCAGCGACCCCAGCCUGAACGAGAAGUGGCAGGAGCACCGGCGCUCACUAGAGCUGAGCAGCCUGGCUGGCCCUGGAGAGGAUCCCCUUUCUGCCGACAGCCUAGGGAAGCCCACCAGAGUGCCGGGGGGUGCCGAGCUUUCUGUUGCAGCCGGAGUAGCUGAGGGGCAGAUGGAGAACAUCUUGCAGGAGGCCACCAAAGAGGAGAGUGGAGUAGAGGAACCUGCCCACAGGGCAGGCAUUGAGAUACAGGAGGGUAAAGAGGACCCUCUCUUAGAAAAGGAGAGCAGGAGGAAGACACCUGAGGCCUCAGCCAUUGGACUUCACCAAGACCCAGAACUGGGUGAUGCUGCUCUGAGGAGCCAUCUGGAUAUGAGCUGGCCUCUGUUCUCACAGGGCAUUUCUGAACAGCAGAGUGGGCUCAGUGUUCUCCUCAGUUCUCUCCAGGUCCCCCCCAGGGGAGAGGAUUCCCUGGAGGUCCCUGUGGAGCAGUUUCGAAUAGAAGAGAUUGCAGAGGGUAGGGAGGAAGCAGUUCUUCCAAUCCCAGUAGAUGCAAAAGUUGGCUAUGGUACCUCACAGUCAUGUUCUCUGCUACCUUCCCAAGUCCCUUUUGAGACCAGAGGACCAAACGUGGACAGUUCUACAGACAUGUUAGUGGAAGAUAAGGUGAAGUCAGUAAGUGGGCCCCAAGGUCAUCAUAGAUCUUGCCUUGUAAAUAGUGGCAAGGACAGGCUUCCUCAGACCAUGGAACCCAGCCCUUCAGAGACAAGCCUGGUCGAGAGGCCCCAAGUGGGGUCUGUGGUGCAUAGGACUUCCCUUGGCAGCACUCUCAGCCUGACACGUUCCCCUUGUGCCUUGCCUUUAGCCGAAUGUAAAGAGGGGCUUGUGUGCAAUGGUGCCCCAGAGACUGAAAACAGGGCCUCAGAGCAGCCCCCAGGUCUUAGCACCCUCCAGAUGUACCCCACACCCAAUGGGCAUUGCGCCAAUGGGGAGGCUGGUAGGAGCAAGGACUCACUGAGCCGUCAGCUGUCUGCUAUGAGCUGCAGCUCUGCCCACUUACACUCAAGGAACUUGCACCACAAGUGGCUGCAUAGCCACUCAGGAAGGCCAUCUGCAACCAGCAGCCCCGACCAGCCUUCCCGCAGCCACCUGGACGAUGAUGGCAUGUCAGUGUACACAGACACGAUCCAACAGCGCCUGCGUCAGAUUGAGUCAGGCCACCAGCAGGAAGUAGAAACUUUGAAGAAACAAGUCCAGGAGCUGAAGAGUCGCCUGGAGAGCCAGUACCUGACCAGCUCCCUACACUUUAAUGGAGACUUUGGGGAUGAGGUGACUUCAAUCCCCGACUCGGAAAGCAAUCUGGAUCAGAACUGUUUGUCUCGCUGCAGCACAGAGAUUUUCUCUGAAGCCAGCUGGGAGCAGGUGGAUAAACAGGACACAGAGAUGACCCGUUGGCUUCCUGACCACCUGGCCGCCCACUGCUAUGCGUGCGACAGUGCCUUCUGGCUUGCCAGCAGGAAGCACCACUGCAGGAAUUGUGGGAACGUAUUCUGCUCCAGUUGUUGUAACCAGAAGGUUCCAGUUCCCAGCCAGCAGCUCUUUGAACCCAGUCGAGUAUGCAAGUCUUGCUAUAGCAGCCUACAUCCCACAAGCUCCAGCAUUGACCUUGAACUGGAUAAGCCCAUUGCUGCCACUUCCAACUGAAGCUCAGUGACCUGGGUGGGCAGUGGCCAAGCUGCUGUUCCUAUGACAGGCCCACUCAACCUGGGCAGACCGAGAGGCCCGUGCACUUUGGAAUGGGAGCGUGGAACCACCUGUACAGAGUGACAGAUUUGGGAUGCACCACUGGAUUGUAGAUUGAUUUUUCUUUCCUGUCCCCCUACUCCCUCCCUACCUUUUCCAUCCUCCUCCUCUGCCUUCAAAAAAGGAAACUUUCCCUUGGUUGUCUUAAUUUUUUUUUUUUUUGAUGGAAGACCAAGGGUUGCCAGGCCCACUGUAACUGCCGAGCUGCCUGCUGUCACGUGACACUGAGGGAUGGCUUGUUUCUUCCGGGUGGGAGGAUGGUGGUCAGAGCCAGGAGUAUGGAGAUCUGAGACCGUGAGCAGGGAAGAAAGCCAGUGCUAACAUGCAACCAUUCCUCACGCCACCGCCACAUCAGAGCUGGUUGGGAACCCUUUGCUGCUGGGGAGGCUGGAAGCAUAUUCCCCAAGAGCACUGCCCUGGGCAUCAUCUCCCUCCUGCGAGGAGCUGAGCCAGUCCCCUCACAGAUGGAUAAAUGAGGCUGAUGUUUGGAGGGAGAGGCACACGGUAAAUGGCAUCCCCUUAGGCGCCUCUUUGGGAAAGGAAAGUGGAUGCUCCUUUGAGGCAGGCGAGGGGCUGGGAGUGGGUAGCCGUCAUGUUGUCCCCCGUGGGAUCCCAUUUUUAACUUGACCCAGAUUGUCUUGGGCUCCUUUUACUUUCAGGGGGCUGCUUUCCUGGGCCAGGCUGUGUAGCACUUCCCACCCUCAGGCAUGAGUACAGACUGGUCAAAAUGUUUAUGCAGUCAAGGCCAAAGCCUGCCCUGAGCCCAGACACACCUGGGUCCCCAUUCUGGGGCCUGGUCCCCUAAACAAUCUCUUCCUCAGCCAGCACAGGGAAAUCCAGACUCAGGGUUCCAGAAAUCCCCCGUUCCCAAACCAAACCAAUCAUGGAUCUUCCCUUUAAGGGGUAGAAUCAGCCUUUAGAGUUACAAGCCCCUGGAAAAGGGAGCAGGUCCCAUACAAUCAGCCUUUCUCCUCUUCUCUUCUUGGGACAGGAAUAACUGCUGAGCAGUCCCCCUUUGCCACUCCUGGCUGUCUGAGUGGGCACUUGUCUGGCUGCUGGCCAGCAGUGAAGGGCCACUUGGUGACUUCGUAGGGUUCCUUAGAGAAGUGACAUGGCCUUGAGGAGAUUCAGGGCACCUUUCCUCAGUGAGCUUUGAUAUGGUCCAAAAACAGCCUUAAAUCAAGAAUAUUUGUGGAGGUAGGUGUGGGGAAGGUUGGAGAAGAGUUAGGUUUGUGCUUUGUAAUCUUGGCAUCCAUGUUUUGUGCCUGCCCUCCCUCUUGGGGAGGCCAUGCUUGACUCUGCUGAAAGCUGCUAACUGGUGACAGGGUGGAUCAUGGUGAGGACUAGGGGUAAGGUCAGGGAAUGCUUAAGCUCUGGCCCUGCCCUGUAUUCCUCUUCCCCUUGGUAGCAGUUCCCUGACCAAGGGCAAGGUGUGUCUCAGGAAGGUGGUUCUGUGCAUGCCUGGGUGUGGUUAAGGCGUGGCCCAGAAGGCUUCCCUGGUGCUCUCAGUCCAGGCAAAGCCCAGAGCAUCUGAGCACGUCUCUGACUUCCAGUGGCAACACAGUUUGAACGUGGUGAAACAGGGUGUAGUUCUUUUCCACAUUCUGUGUCAUCUAGUCGUGCAGGUAGGGAAAAAGUUGGUCUAAUUGAAGAUUGUGCAUUUCCUAGUGACAGGUGCCAAGAGGUUAUGAUACGGGUUUCUUGGGUCUGAUGUACAGUGUGAAUAAAUGCUUGCAGCUCUUAGCUCUUUUUUGAUCGAUGAAGCACUUUUUUAUUAAUAUUUUCCUUUGUUAAAGGAGGAACCGUAACUCUCCAUAGCUGUACAUAUAACCCUUUUCUCCUAAAGAGGAGUCAGUCAGUGCUCCUAUAUUUUUCAUUUUUUGUCAAAGCAAGAAGUAAAUACUUUAGAAUUGUUAAAUAUAUAAAUAAAGCAAAUAAAGUUGAGUGUUCCACAUGGUAGCAUUUGCUAACACUUCCUAAUUCUUUGCCCUGUGGUUUAUCCCCUCUUCGUCCCUUUUCCCUCUCACACAGAAGUGUUUGAGGGCCUGCUGGGAAACUGACCUUUGGCAAAGGAAAGCUACAGAUAGCCUUCCGACUCUAGACCUUGGCAAGGAGCCUCACCAUGAUGUUCAAGCACUGAACGCAUUUCCUCAGUGAUUUUGCUCCUAAAAUCUCCCAGGCUAAAAGAGGGCAAAGCAGUCAGGGAUCUGACCUGGCAGCUAUUCCUCCUUCUCUGAAGAGUUCCCAUCAGUAGUCAUUACAACUACCUCUCGCCUCAAGGCUCCAUUUUUAGCUGCUGCUCUGAUUUCAGGGCAGCCAGUACUCUGGCCCCUUCAGUCGGGGAGUGGAAGGAGAUGUGGGGUGGGGGUGAGAAAAUGCUUCUGCCUGUUGUUCUUGAAGGAUAGACUAUGGGUGGGCAGAGAGAACUGGGGGCAGAAAUGGAAUUAGAUGUGAUUGGGUUAUGCAGUCAACUAGAGGUCUCCUUCCCGCCCUCUCUCCACACAGAGAGGAACCUCUGCUCCUUAGCUCUUACAGCAGGACUGUGGCAUCUAGUCACUUCAAUACUAGUUCUUGCUCUUCACAGAGGUAGAUUUUUCUUUACCCUACAGCACUGUUGGGCAUCCCUCCCAUCACAUGGGUCUGUGGGUGAGAUAUGUUAUGCUGUUCCUCCCUCGGGAAGGUUGGUAUUGAGGGGUGCCUUGCUCCAGAGGCGCCAGCCCAGCAUCUGUGGUGAGUUGGCUAAGAUCCAGAGUGACCUGCUCAGAGCUCCCCAGAGGCCUUCACUCUUUGGGGCAGUCUCUCUAGGGUCACUUUCUGAAUGUACCUUCUACCUAAAGUAUACAAACACAAAGAGCCAGCUGAGCUGGUUCUAGUGUGAAAGCCGUAAGUGCCACCCAGCAGGCGUUUGAAAACAAGAAAUCAUUCUUCUGUGGAAGGAGAAUGUGCCAUCUCAGCUACCCUCAGUCCGCCAGGCAGCCCAGUCUGUGUAUUCAUAUGAAGUUGUGAAAACCAUGAGUGUGUGCCAUGGCCAUCGUGUCUACACACAGCCACUAUUGUUCCUGUGGGCUAGUCUCCAGCAAAUUAAAACACUGGCAUGGCCUAGGAAGGGCGUUGCGAGCUCCUAAAUGGAAAGCUUCUCUGGGGGUAGGGAGAUGAAGAGCCAAGAUGCUGGUGAAGCAGGUGCAGUGAGGAUCCAAGGCAAGGAAUUGCCCUGAGGGAGGUGGCUGCAUAUGGAGAAAGGCAGUUCUCUGUGGGCAAGGCCAGCUUGCUUCAGGCUGUAGAGGGAAUUUGGUCUGAAGCAACAGGGCAUGAACUGUGACUUUGAGCUGCCAGGUUGUCUUCAUCUCAGAACUUUCCUAUCCUGGCACUCUCGUUACCUUUCUUCUAUACCUUGGCCUCUGUAACUGCAGUCCAAAACAAGUUACAGCUGCCUUAAUCCACUGAGAUUCUCUAUGAGGAUGUACAGAAAAGUUUUCCUGUAAUAAUUUUGCUUAUAUGCUAACUCUUUUCAUGUUAGCAAAGAAUAUUCUAUGAAUUAGAAUGUUACUGUGGUAGAUCUAAAGGAGAAUGAACAGAAGGUGCUGGAGGACCUGUUAAACAAUCUCUGGCUAUUAAAAAACAUCAAGAUGAGAAUUAAAGGCAUAUCCUGAUAUACUUGCCUGCUUGCACAUGAGGCUGGGAGAUCCCAUGCCUGUUGAAGUUAACUCUAGCCCUGACCUCUAUUGAUCUUUUGGGAAUGAGGGCUGAUUUGAAGGUGCUGUUGCAGGAUUUCAUUUAGCUGCUGCCAGUUCAAGUGACCUGUCCCCAGGGCUGCAGCUGUAUCCACCUGAUUGCAGUAGGUGAGGGCUAACAGCAGAAUUUAAAGUGGACCCUGGGCUGUGGAGCAAAGUGACUAUCCAUUUGGACUUUUGGAUAAUGUGGCAGGAGUCCCAGCUGUUUAAUUUCUAGUCACAUUUUCCAGAAAGUUGUUCUAAGUUGAGAUUACUGACAAGAUUUCUCAAGGGCAGGACCAGAUAUGUGAGAGACUUCUAGUUCAGAGCUGACCCCUCUAAGCCUCUGACACUUAAACACGAGUCCUGCUGUCCCCAGCACACAACUGCACUGAAGCCUUGUUCCUCUCGGCUGGUGUAGAGCUCAUCUGCAUGUUGUGUGCAGAUACCAGUAGCCUCCCUGCUUGAACAGGCCUCUCCUAGGCUAGGCAGGUGUUCAGAGGCAUGAAGGUCUGGGCAGGGGAAGGGCGUCUUCUGAAAUGGGAGUUACCAGGUUUUUAAAUGCUGCUAUUGUUUUAUUUACCAUUUAAGGUCUUUUCUAUUAUAUCUGAGUAACUAGUCAGUUUUUCUUACAGUGCUCAUAGCAGUUGUAUUUGAAUUGUAUUUUCAGUGAAAUUUGUUUUACAUUGCCAUUUAAAAUUGGCCUUUAACAGCUUCCCAACUAGCUUAUAAGAUUUUUUUUUUUAAUGAAAACAUAACCCAUGAGGCUCAGAUGCUGUUGAAGAAAUAAAUGGUAUGUUGCUGCUGACAGUAGUGCUUGCCUAUUGUAACAGCAUUGGUUCUGCUGUAGCCUCGGUGACCAUUUAAGUUGAAUAAAUCUGUCAUUUUCACCCACAAACAGUUGUUGAGCCCCUGGAUUUGGGUUGUCACUGUGGUUCUCCUGCCAGUGCUAUAAUCCAGUGUCGUAGGUGCAGGGUAUGAAUCAGCUCAGCCUCUUAGGAGAGAGGGGCUCUCAGCGAGGAGGGGGCGGGGGGGGGGUCACUAUUUAUCUUCCAGAGGCAGGGUUCAUGGAUUCCUGAUGUUUAGAGGCGGAAGGGACCUUAGGUCACCUACUUCCACGGUUUUCAUACUGUUCUCUGGGGCCUCGUGGAGAGGGAGCCUCCAGGCCCAUUCAAAGCUUUAUUAGAUUUAAAAGUAAGAUCUGGUAUGAAGAAAGGUUUUGUUUGUUUCUUAAAAUAAAAAGUCUGAAAAUCACUAA